ACUUUCACUUUCUCUUCCGCCGAAGCCGCUCCCCUUGCGAAGAACUGGGGCCUCCCGGGAGGAGAGAGGGCUUUGCCUUGAAACCCGGGACGCCAGGGGCGCUCCCGCAAGUGGGGGUCCUCCGGGACUUGGAACGCCCCGGCUGGGUGGUGUCCGGGCGUCCUUUCCCCGCUUCUUCCCACCUCGGCUGGUCCCGUUUCCUCCUGCGCCCAGUGCGGACCUGUCUCGGCGCCCGCUGCCCUCUCACCGCCCCACGCAGGAUCCCGGCCUGGUCACCGGGCAGUGUGAUGCUUCCCGACUGCCGCGGGGACAGCGAGGCACACACAGGGCUUGGGCCGCGCCGGAGGCCACACGGCCUGGCUGAGUUGCUCCUGGUCUCCCGCCUCUCCCAGGCGACCCGGAGGUAGCAUUUCCCAGGAGGCACGGUCCCCCCCAGGGGGAUGGGCACAGCCACGCCAGAUGGACGAGAAGACCAAGAAAGCUCCUGAAAAUAAACCCUGUGCUAACUGGCUCCUGCUGUACUGGCUUUCAGCAGAGGAAAUGGCCCUGAGCCUCACCCGAGCAGUGGCGGGCGGGGAUGAACAGGUGGCAAUGAAGUGUGCCAUCUGGCUGGCAGAGCAACGGGUGCCCCUGAGUGUGCAACUGAAGCCUGAGGUCUCCCCAACGCAGGACAUCAGGAGCAGGGGAGAGAAGACAGAAGAGGUUGGAGAGGUCAGGGAGGUGCCAGAUCAUGGAGGCCCUCGUGUGCUGCCACGAGUUGAUUCUAAGAGUAGCGUGGAGCCAUUGGAGGGGCCUAACUGGCUGUGGGUGAGCGUGGAGGAUGCUCAGAUGCACACCGUCACCAUCUGGCUCACAGUGCGCCCUGAUAUGACAGUGGCGUCUCUCAAGGACAUGGUUUUUCUGGACUAUGGCUUCCCACCAGUCUUGCAGCAGUGGGUGAUUGGGCAGCGGCUGGCACGAGACCAGGAGACCCUGCACUCCCAUGGGGUGCGGCAGAAUGGGGACAGUGCCUACCUCUAUCUGCUGUCAGCCCGCAACACCUCCCUCAACCCUCAGGAGCUGCAGCGGGAGCGGCAGCUGCGGAUGCUGGAAGAUCUGGGCUUCAAGGACCUCACGCUGCAGCCGCGGGGCCCUCUGGAGCCAGGCCCCCCAAAGCCCGGGGUCCCCCAGGAACCCGGACGGGGGCAGCCAGAUGCAGUGCCUGAGCCCCCACCGGUGGGCUGGCAGUGCCCCGGGUGCACCUUCAUCAACAAGCCCACGCGGCCUGGCUGUGAGAUGUGCUGCCGGGCGCGCCCCGAGGCCUACCAGGUCCCCGCCUCAUACCAGCCCGACGAGGAGGAGCGAGCGCGCCUGGCGGGCGAGGAGGAGGCGCUGCGUCAGUACCAGCAGCGGAAGCAGCAGCAGCAGGAGGGGAACUACCUGCAGCACGUCCAGCUGGACCAGAGGAGCCUGGUGCUGAACACGGAGCCCGCCGAGUGCCCCGUGUGCUACUCGGUGCUGGCGCCCGGCGAGGCCGUGGUGCUGCGUGAGUGUCUGCACACCUUCUGCAGGGAGUGCCUGCAGGGCACCAUCCGCAACAGCCAGGAGGCGGAGGUCUCCUGCCCCUUCAUUGACAACACCUACUCGUGCUCGGGCAAGCUGCUGGAGAGGGAGAUCAAGGCGCUCCUGACCCCUGAGGAUUACCAGCGAUUUCUAGACCUGGGCAUCUCCAUUGCUGAAAACCGCAGUGCCUUCAGCUACCAUUGCAAGACCCCAGAUUGCAAGGGAUGGUGCUUCUUUGAGGAUGAUGUCAAUGAGUUCACCUGCCCUGUGUGUUUCCACGUCAACUGCCUGCUCUGCAAGGCCAUCCAUGAGCAGAUGAACUGCAAGGAGUAUCAGGAGGACCUGGCCCUGCGGGCUCAGAACGAUGUGGCUGCCCGGCAGACGACAGAGAUGCUGAAGGUGAUGCUGCAGCAGGGCGAGGCCAUGCGCUGCCCCCAGUGCCAGAUCGUGGUACAGAAGAAGGACGGCUGCGACUGGAUCCGCUGCACCGUCUGCCACACCGAGAUCUGCUGGGUCACCAAGGGCCCACGCUGGGGCCCUGGGGGCCCAGGAGACACCAGCGGGGGCUGCCGCUGCAGGGUAAAUGGGAUUCCUUGCCACCCAAGCUGUCAGAACUGCCACUGAGCUAAAGAUGGUGGGGCCACAUGCUGACCCAGCCCCACAUCCACAUUCUGUUAGAAUGUAGCUCAGGGAGCUUCGUGGACGGCCUUGCUUGCUGUAGCGUUGUAGGGGCCCUGCCUGCACUGCGGUUGUCCACGGUCACAUCUGCCCCAGUGCCUUUGUCCUUCCCUUGGGGCUUGCCGGCCAGACUUCUCUCCCCUGCGGCUCCCACCUCUGCCUGACCCCAGCCUUAAACAUAGCCCCUGGCCAGAGGCCUUGCUGGGUGGAGCCUCUGUGUGACUCCAUACUCCUCCCACCACAACACUCAUCUGUCAAACACCAAGCACUCUCAGCCUCCCCGCCUUCAGCUGUCAGCUUUCUGGGGCUAACUUCUCUGCCUUUGUGGUUGGAGGCCUGAGGCCUCUUGGAACUCUUGCUAACCUGUUCAGAGCCAGGAAGGAGACUGCACAGUUUUGAAAGCACAGCCCGUCAGGUCCGGCUCUGCGUCUCCCUCUCUGCAGCCUGUGUAAGCUAUUAUAAUUAAAAUGGUUUUCCGGGAAGGGAUGAGUGUGAUGUCCUUGAGAGGAAAUGAAUGUCCUGGCCUGGGACUCUACACACAGGCAGGAUCCUGAGGUCUCUGGGAACUGCAUCAGAAAGUUGACUUGUCAGUCCAUCUGUGGUAGAAUGAGGCUGUGACUGAGCACUGGGACCUUUCUACCAGAUGUGGACCCCAUGCCCAGCCUCAGGGGCAAGGAUGCUCUUGGGUCACCGUCAGCCAGGACAGGUGGAGUGUGCAGUGUGUCAAGUCUGCAGAGAAGGAUGGGCUUAGGGGCGGGAGGGGAAGUCUUGCCACUCCUGCUCCCUUUUGACCUCUCAGCAGGCAUCUAGGGUUGGCAGGUAGAUAGUUCAAGAAGGAACGAAGCUGCUGCAGUUGAGGGGUGGGGUUGUCCAUCCUAUUUUCUCGUCUCAAGCAAGAUGGCACAGUAUCGAUUCAGCAGUAUUUACUAGAACCCACUCUGUGCUGGUCGGAGGUUACUAAGACAGGGUCCUGGGAUGUUCAUUCUCUAAGUCUUUCCUCCGCUCUGUGACCCACCCUCCUUCCCCUUUUGAGAUCUGGUAUUUGAUGCCCAACACAUUGUCCACGCUGUGACGUGACCAUCAUCAUAGCAGGCAGAGGGCGCCUCUGCUGCUGAAGGCCUGUGAUUUUGUGGGGAAGGGCCUGUUCUAGCAACUGGAAAGGCACUGCCACCUGCCGUUGGAUGCCAGGACUCAAGAGCUGGCCCCAGUCACUGUGCGCAGAGCUGUCUGAGAAUGUGUGAGUGGACUGGGUCCUUCGGCACUGCCUGCAUUGGCUCAGGGCAGUCAACCGUCGCAGAGGAUGAGGGGCACACUCAGGCAGCCUCCCCGGCCCUGGAGGCAGAAAGGCCCAGGCAGAACCACUGACUGGGAGGAAACAGAAAAAGCAGAGGAGAGCCAGGCUGCAGGCGUGUGGAUGGGACCAGCUCAGGCAGACGCUGUCUCAUACCCACUCUCCCCUCUCUUGCCAGGGCCUGGCCUGGUGUCUCUCAGGAGCCUGGGCAUGAGACAAAAGCAGAGAUUGUUCUCUUGUGGUACCACAGGCUGUAACCAGUCCACCCAGUGUUGUUUUAGAAAUUUAAAUCGGUUGCCCAUCUUUUUAAAUUGGCAACAUCGUUUACCACAUUAAAAUCUAGAUGCCCUGCUUCUCUUGAAAA